GCAGAUUCGCGAAAACCCGGAAGCGGAUCGCGUGGAGUGACGGUCCCACGGCAGCGCGAUUGACUUCUAAAGACUCUUGGUAUGUGAGGAAGAAACCUGGAAGAGGAAGAGGAAAGCAAAGGAGUCAGGGAUGGCUCUUCCUCAGGGUCUAUUGACAUUCAGGGAUGUGGCCAUAGAAUUCUCUCAGGAGGAGUGGAAAUGCCUGGACCCUGCUCAGAGGACUCUAUACAGGGACGUGAUGCUGGAGAAUUAUAGGAACCUGGUCUCCCUGGAUAUCUCUUCCAAAUGCAUGAUGAAGGAGUUCUCAUCAACAGCACAAGGCAAUAGAGAAGUGAUCCACACAGGGACAUUGCAAAGACAUGAAAGUCAUCACACUGGAGACUUUCGCUUUCAGGAAAUUGAUAAAGAUAUUCAUAACUUAGAGUUUCAGUGGCAAGAAGAUGAAAGAAAUAGCCAUGAAGCACCCAUGACAGAAAUCAAAAAGUUGACUGGUAGUGCAGACCGAUAUGAUCAAAGGCAUGCUGGAAACAAGCCUAUUAAAGAUCAGCUUGGAUCAAGCUUUCAUUCGCAUCUGCCUGAACUCCACAUGUUUCAGACCCAAGGGAAAAUUGGUAAUCAAGUGGAGAAGUCUAUCAACGAUGCUUCCUCAAUUUCAACAUCCCAAAGAAUUUCUUGUAGGCCCAAAACCCAUAUUUCUAAUAACUAUGGGAAUAAUUUCCGGAAUUCUUCGUUACUCACACAAAAACAGGAGGUACACAUGAGAGAAAAGUCUUUCCAAUGUAAUGAGAGUGGCAAAGCCUUUAAUUAUAGCUCACUCUUAAGGAAACAUCAAAUAAUCCAUUUAGGAGAGAAACAAUAUAAAUGUGAUGUAUGUGGCAAGGUCUUUAAUCGGAAGCGAAACCUAGUGUGCCAUCGUAGAUGUCACACUGGGGAGAAACCUUACAGGUGUAAUGAGUGUGGCAAGACUUUCAGUCAGACGUAUUCCCUUACAUGCCAUCGUAGACUUCAUACUGGAGAGAAACCUUACAAAUGUGAAGAAUGUGACAAAGCUUUCAGUUUCAAAUCAAACCUUAAAAGACAUAGGAGAAUUCAUGCUGGAGAAAAACCAUACAAGUGUAAUGAAUGUGGCAAGACCUUUAGUCAGACGUCAUCCCUUACAUGCCAUCGUAGACUUCAUACUGGAGAGAAACCUUUCAAGUGUAAUGAGUGUGGCAAGACCUUUAGUCGGAAGUCAUCCCUUACAUGCCAUCAUAGACUUCAUACGGGAGAGAAACCUUAUAAGUGUAAUGAAUGUGGCAAGACCUUCAGUCAGGAGUUAACCCUUAAAUGCCAUCGUAGACUUCAUACCGGAGAGAAGCCUUACAAGUGUAAUGAAUGUGGCAAGGUUUUUAAUAAAAAGGCAAACCUUGCACGUCAUCAUAGACUUCAUAGUGGAGAGAAACCCUACAAGUGUACUGAGUGUGUCAAGACGUUCAGUCGAAAUUCAGCCCUUGUAAUUCAUAAGGCUAUUCAUAUUGGAGAGAAACGUUACAAGUGUAAUGAGUGUGGCAAGACGUUCAGUCGAAUUUCAGCCCUCGUAAUUCAUACGGCAAUUCAUACUGGAGAGAAACCUUACAAGUGUAAUGAAUGUGGCAAGGGUUUUAAUCGGAAAACACACCUUGCAUGUCAUCAUAGACUUCAUACUGGAGAGAAACCUUACAAGUGUAAUGAAUGUGGCAAGGUUUUUAAUCGAAAAACACACCUUGCACAUCAUCAUAGACUUCAUACUGGAGAUAAACCUUACAAGUGUAAUGAAUGUGGCAAGGUUUUUAAUCAAAAAGCACACCUUGCACGUCACCAUAGACUUCAUACUGGAGAGAAACCUUACAAGUGUAAUGAAUGUGGCAAGGUUUUUAAUCAAAAAGCAAACCUUGCACGUCAUCAUAGACUUCAUACUGGAGAGAAACCUUACAAGUUUAAUGAGUGUGGCAAAGCUUUUAAUUGAAAAGCAAAGCUUGCACAUCAUCAUACAAUUCAUACUGGAAAGAAACAAGUGCAAUGAGUGUGGCAAGACCUUCUGUCACAAUUCAGUCCUUGUAAUUCAUAAGAAUUCAUACUGGAGAGAAACAAGUGUAAUGAACGUUGCAAAAUUUUUAAUCAACAAGCACACCUUCCACGUCAUCAUAGACUUCAUAGUGGAGAGAAACCUUAGAAAUGUGAAGCAUGUGACAAAGUUUACAGUGGCAAAUCGAGCCUCAAAAGACAGGAGAAUUCAUACUGGAGAGAAAGCUUACAAAGGUGAAGAAUAUCACAGAGUUUUCAGUCACAAGUCAAACCUUGAAAGACAUAAAAUAAAUCAUACUGCAGAGAAACCAUAAAAUUGUAAGAGUUCGUGACAAGGCUUUCGGGCAUGACUCACACCUGGCACAACAUCCUAGAAUUUAUACUGGAGAGAAACCUUACAAGUGUAAUGAGUCUGGCAAAGCCUUAAUGAGCAGUCAACACUUACUCACCAUCAGGCAAUCCAUGGUGAAGGAAACUUGACUAAUGUAAUGAUUGUCACCAAGUCUUCAGUAACGCUACAACCAUUGCAAAUCAUUGGAGAACCCAUAAGGAAGAGAGAUCAUACAAGUGUAAUAAUCGGCAAAUUUUUCAGACAUCGUCCAUACCUUGCAGUUCAUUGGCGAACUCAUACUGGAGACAAACCUUAUAAAUGUCAUGAUUGAGGCAAGGUCUUCAGUCAAGCUUCAUCCUAUGCAAAACAUAGGAGAAUUCAUACAGGAGAGAAACCUCACGUGUGAUGAUUGUGGCAAAGCCUUUACUUCACGUUCACACCUCCUUAGACAUCAGAGAAUGCACACUGGACGGAAAUCUUACAAAUGUCAUCAGUGUGGCAAGGUUUUCAGUCUGACUUCACUCCUUGCAGAAUAUCAGAAAAUUCAUUUUGAGAUAAUUGUUCCAAAUGCAAUGAGUAGAGCAAACCAUCAAGCAGUAAUUGACAUUAAAGUGUUUAUGUUAAGAGGAUUGGGCCAGGUACAGUGUCUCACACCUGUAAUCCCAGCACUUUGGGAGGCCAAGGCGGGUAGAUCACUUGAGGUCAGGAGUUUCAGAUCAGUCUGGCCAACAAACAUGAGCCACUUUUCCCAGUUUGCUUUUUGUUCUUUAACAAAAACUGAUAGGGAUUUUUAUGGGUACCGUGUUGAAUCUAAAUCACAUUGGGUUAUAUAAUCAUUUAACAAUAUUAAUUUUUCCAAUCCAUCAAUAUGGGUUAUAUGUCUGUAUAUGUUUUUAAUCAUAUUGAUGUAUAUUUGUAGAUUUCAAGGUACAAACUUCUCACCUUUUUACUUUUAUUUCUAUUUCUUUAAGUUCUCUAGCAAAUGGAAGUGUUUUUAAAUUUUCUUUUAAAAUUGUUUAUUGUUACAAACUUCUCAUCUUUUUGCUUUUAUUCCUAAGUAUUUCUUACUUUAAGUUCUCUAGCAAAUGGAAGUGUUUUUAAAUUUUCUUUUAAAAUUGUUUAUUGUUAAUGUAUGGAAAUUCAGCUAAUUUUUGGUGCUGAUAUUGUACUGUGCAGAUACACUGAAUCUGUUUAUUACUUCCAGUAGUAUUUUGGUUGAGUCUUUGUGAUUUUCUACACAGAAGAUCAUGUCAUCUACAAACACAUAUAAUUUUACUUCUUUCUUUCUGAUUUGGAUGGGUUUGAUUUCUUUUGCUAUUUCAUUGCUCUGGCUAGGACAGCCAGUAUUUAUUGAAUAGAAGGGGUGAGAGCAUUCUUCCAUCAUGUGAGAUCCUACAGGAAAAUCAUUCCAUGUUCCCUGCUUCGUUAUCUACUCGUUGGUCAUUUCAUGGAUGGCCUUUCUAUUGUUGAGGUAAAUUUCCUUUUCUGUCUAUUUUGUUCAGAAUUUCUAUGAUGAGUGGAUUUUGAAUUUUGUGAAAUACUUUUUCUCCAUCUAUUGAGAUGAUGUGGUUUUCAUCUUUCAUUCUGUUCAAGUGGCAUAUCACAUUGAUUUGCUUGACUAUGUUGAACCAUCCUUGCAUCCCAGAAAUAAGUGGCACUUGAGUAUCUACAGUCCUUUUUACAUCCUCUUGAAUACAGCUUUUUAGUACAAGGGGUCUUCAAGAAGUUCAUGGAAAAAUACAUAUUUUGCAUAUUAUGAGAAAAUUGUGUAUGAAUUUCCCAGUUUUUGCACCAAAAUAAACUGGUACGAAUCUGUUAUGUCUGAACAGGUCCUAGUUUGAGGCACCCAGAAGGAUAAGACAUGAGUUUUAAAAGAGACUUUCUCUGCCGGGCGCAGUGGCUCAUGCCUGUAAUCCCAACACUUUGGGAGGCCAAGGUGGGUGGAUCACCUGAGAUCCAGAGUUCGAGACCAGCCUCACCAACAUGGAGAAACAGCAUCUCUACUAAAAAUACAAAAUUAGCCAGGCAUGGUGGCAAAUGCCUGUAAUCCCAGAUACUCUGGAGGCUGAGGCAGGAGAAUGGCUUGAACCCGGGAGGCAGAGAUUGCUGUGAGCCGAGAUUGCACCAUUGCACUCCAGCCUGGUCAACAAGAGCGAAACUCUGUCUCAAAAAAAAAAAAAAGAAAAGAAAAGAAAAGAGACUCUAUCAAAGCAAUAUAAAUCCUGCUAAAAUUGAAACAAAAAGGAGCAUCAAAUUUACAGUGAGACCAGAUGCAGUGGCUCAGGCCUGUAAUCCCAGCACUUUCAGAGGCCAAGACAGGUGGGUCAUGUAAGCCCAGGUAUUCAAGACAAGCCUGGGCAACAUGGUGAAACCCCCUUGUCUACAAAAAAUACAAAAAUUAGCUGGGCACGGUAGCACAUGCAUGCAGGGCCAGCUGCUGUGGAGUCUGUGGUAGGAGGAUAGCUCGAGCCUGGGAGGUUGAGGCUGCAGUGAGCUAUGAUCAUGCCACUGCAUUCCAGCAUGGGUGAUGGAGCGAGAUACUGGCUCAAAAAAAAAAAUACUUCUUGUAAAGUUUGGGUAGAGGAAUAAUGAAAUCAUUGAUGCUUUAUGAAAAGAUUAUGGAGAUGAUGCCCAGAAGAAAUAAACAGUUUGUAAAUGGAUAACUUAGUUUGAGUUGGGACAAGACAAUGUUGAAGGUGAUGCAUGGAGUGGCAGGCACACCAUCCACAUCAGUUUUUUUGUUUGUUUUUGUUGUUGUUGUUUUUUUGAGAUGGUGUCUCGCUCUGUCUCCCAGGCUGGAAUGCAGUGGUGCAAUCUCGGCUCACUGCAACCUCUGCCUCCCGGGUUCAAGUGAUUCUCCUGUCUCUGCCUCCUUAGUAGCUGGGACUACAGGCGCGUGCCACCACAUCAGCUAAUUUUUGUAUUUUUAGUAAGACGGGGUUUCACCAUGUUGGCAAGGCUGGUCUUGAACUCCUGACCUCACGAUCUGCCCACCUCAGCCUCCCAAAGUGUGGAGAUUACAGGCAUGAGCCACCAUGCCCCUUGCACAUCAGUUUUACAAAAAAAUUUAUCUUGUUUGUGCCACAAUGAAGAGGACUGACAGGUAACAGCAGAAACAAUAGUCAGGAGUUUGAGAACAGGCUGAUUAACAUGGUGAAACCCCGUCUCUACUAAAAAUACAAAAAUUAGCUGGGUGUGGUGGCGGGUGCUUGUAAUCCCAGUUACUCAGGAGGCUGAGGCUGCAUUAUCGCUUUAACCUGGGGGGCGGAGGUUGCAGUGAGCCAAGAUGGGGGCAAUAAGAGCAAAACUUUGUCUCAAAAAAAAAUAAAUAAAUAAAAAAUAAAAUAUGUCAAGCCCCUUCUCUUCCUGUCUCCUCUCGUGGUGUGUACUUGACUCCCCUUCUCGCCAGAUCUCACAGGACUUUCAGAUUUAAGCAAUACCUGGCCAAGAAACAAAAGCAAAAUCAUUCCAUUCCCCCAGUGGAUUCAGAUCAAAACUGGUAAUAAAAUCAGGUACGACUCCAAAAGGAGACAUUGGAGAAGAACGAAGCGGGGUCUAUAAGGAAUUGCACGUGAGAUGGCACACAUAUUUAUGCUGUGUGAGCAUUACAAUCGCGUUACCAUAUCAAGCUGAAAAUGUCACCACUAUCUGGAGUGUUGGAAAUGUUUUAUUGGGAAUAUGUUUUUUCUCUGAAUCUGCUAUGAACACGUCAGUUGGGUGGGUUCAGUAAUAAAUAUGUGAGACUUUUCAUUUCAAAAUAAAAAAGGCAAAUGAUGUAA